ACUUCCGGUACGGAAAACUCGCUGCUGCCCCAACCUGGCUUGACAGGCUUGGUCUCUGCAAGUGGCUCUCAGCCCCUUCUUCUUUCCUGCCUCACCUUCCAAUUCGUUUGCCGCCGCCGUCCCGCAGCUGCUGUUUCCGGAGUUGCCCCUUCCCCAUGUUCCGGGGCAGGAGUCCGCAAAGCGAAGAUCCGCCCGCCGGUUCCUCAUCAUGUCCGAACUGACUAAAGAGCUGAUGGAGCUGGUGUGGGGCACCAAGAGCAGCCCCGGUCUCUCGGACACCAUUUUCUGCCGCUGGACGCAAGGGUUUGUGUUUAGUGAAUCAGAGGGAUCUGCAUUAGAACAGUUUGAAGGUGGCCCCUGUGCUGUUAUUGCACCUGUUCAGGCAUUUCUUUUGAAGAAGCUCCUGUUUUCUUCGGAGAAGUCUUCUUGGCGGGAUUGUUCAGAGGAAGAGCAGAAGGAACUCCUUUGUCAUACCUUGUGUGAUAUUUUAGAAAGUGCUUGUUGUGACCACUCUGGAUCAUACUGCUUGGUUUCAUGGUUAAGAGGAAAGACAACUGAGGAAACUGCUAGUAUUUCUGGGAGUCCUGCAGAGUCUAGUUGCCAAGUGGAACAUUCUUCUGCCUUGGCUGUCGAAGAGCUUGGCUUUGAGCGAUUUCAUGCAUUAAUUCAAAAAAGAUCGUUCAGAAGUUUACCAGAAUUAAAAGAUGCUGUCUUGGACCAGUAUUCAAUGUGGGGAAAUAAAUUUGGAGUAUUGCUUUUUCUGUAUUCUGUAUUACUGACAAAGGGCAUUGAAAACAUAAAAAACGAAAUUGAAGAUGCAAGUGAACCCUUGAUAGAUCCUGUAUAUGGACAUGGCAGCCAAAGUUUAAUUAAUCUCCUGCUGACGGGACAUGCUGUUUCUAAUGUAUGGGAUGGUGAUAGAGAGUGCUCAGGAAUGAAACUUCUUGGUAUACAUGAACAAGCAGCAGUAGGAUUUUUAACACUAAUGGAAGCUUUAAGAUACUGUAAGGUUGGUUCUUACUUGAAAUCUCCAAAAUUCCCUAUUUGGAUUGUUGGCAGUGAGACUCACCUCACCGUAUUUUUUGCCAAGGAUAUGGCUUUAGUUGCCCCUGAAGCUCCUUCAGAACAAGCCAGAAGAGUUUUUCAAACCUACGACCCAGAAGAUAAUGGAUUCAUACCCGAUUCACUUCUGGAAGAUGUGAUGAAAGCAUUGGACCUUGUUUCAGAUCCUGAAUAUAUAAAUCUCAUGAAGAAUAAAUUAGAUCCAGAAGGAUUAGGAAUCAUAUUAUUGGGCCCAUUUCUUCAAGAAUUUUUUCCUGAUCAGAUAUGAGACUGAGAAAACACCGUUACAUGGAAACCUUCCCAGACAGAGGGAAUGUGUGUUCGAAUACGGUAACGCAGUGCCUUGAUGGGGAGGGCAGCAGAAGAUGACGCAGACACCAGUCUAUACACAUAAUGAUACGGAGAGAACAGUUCGGAAGUUUGAGGAGUAAAAAGAGAAAGAUUCUCUUUCUCCACUCCCACCCCCACUUUUCUUCUCUCAGGAAGCUGUUAAAUACUGUGAGAAGAGGUCAAGGUGGCUGUGGGUAGUAGAAGCCCCUAGCUAGUGAAGCUAAGCUCCUGGAGAAUUAAAACCUAAGUGGGUCUGGGCCGUUUCCCAUUGGGACAUGUCUUCCACUGGGCUUUGAUAGGAGCUCAGUUACCUGGAAUAGCAGAGGCAUCUGGGCCAACCUGAAUGUUUUUGAGUUGUAUCUGCAUCAUUGGCAAGCCAGUUCUAUAUCCAAUACCCAUCUUUCUGUCUUUGUUCUCUAAGUGAAGCAUUUUACCACUAAAUCAAAUUACUUAACUAGAUAACAGAUAUCAUGGUCAUUUUAUCAGAUAUCAGUAUAGUUUGCACUGAAGUUCAUUGUUGCAAUAGACAUUCCAAUUUCUAUUUUACCGCUAUUAUUAGAGAGACAUAUUGACAAAUAGAAAAAAUUUAAAAGCAAGAGGGAAAAUUUCAAAAUAUAAUUACUAAAAUUCAGAAUGUAAUUGUUAAAAAAGAUUGUUAAACUCAAGAUAAAAUUGUUAAGAAAGAGGUAAGAUUCAAAAAGUAACUGAGGAUAUCACAAUGUAGACAAUGUAGACUACUGGACUUCUUAAAACUUUGGUCUUAAAGCCUUCAUGAAAAAUUAGAUUUUAUUGUCCGACAUUAGACCCUUCAGUGUGAUAUCCUCUUUGUUCACAUUCUGACUGGAUAUCUGGAUUAAUAAUACAUUAUACCAUCUUAAACUUUGAGACAGUAUUAAUUUUAAUUAUAUUUCAAGGCUGCUAUCGGAACUUUUGAUAGAAAUGUUGAUUCUUAGUUAUAAUAAAAAGAAUAUUCCUGUUUUUAAUUUAAUUUGGGGAAGAUUUUGAAAAGUGAGAAAUGUAAAGUGAGACAGUUACUUGUAGUAAUUUUUUAGGUAAAAAGAGGGUUCUAGUCCCUUCUCUUUCGCCUGUAACAGACAUUUCCAUUUGGUUGUACUGUUUGUUGCCUCUGUGUUCCUCUCUCACUGUUUACUUGUUGCCUGCUAUUCUGAAGACACUCUCCACCUGGGCCUGGUUUGUCUCAUUGUCUGUAUAGUUCAUGCUGUUUGCCUCCCACGAGCAUGUGAUCCUGCUCUUGGUUACCUUUAGAGCAGUGAGUUCUCAGUAUGAUCUCCAAGAGCUUGUUAGAAAUGCUAAUUCUCAGGUUUCUCCCUGAAGCAGAGACUUUAAGGGUGGGUGCAGCAAUGUGGUCUAACAAGCCCUGCAAGUGAUCUGGAGGCCCAAGUUAGAGAACAGCUGCUUUAGAGGAAGACCUGUCACAGUCCCACCUAUUCCCAUCUGUUCCCAUCCUAUAGCAGCUCAGACGCCCUCGGUGUCAUAGAUCUUUUCCGAUCAUGCCCUACAUACCACUGAUGUCCCCUUUCCCCUGUAGCCACAAAAUGCAUAGUGACUCAACACUCCUUUUGGCAAUUAGUCACAUACUGCCUUGUCCCUAACAGAUGAAUAUAGUGAUCAUUCCGUAAACUAUUUAUUUAUUUAAGAUGGAGUUUCGCUCCUUUACCCAGGCUGGAGUGCAGUGGCACGAUCUCAGCUCACUGUAACCUCCGCCUCCCUGGUCCAAGCAAUUCUCCUGCCUCAGCCUCCUGUGUAGCUGGGACUACAUAUGGUGGCCUGGCUAAUUUUUGUAUCCUUAGUAGAGAUGGGGUUUCACCUUGUUGGUCAGGCUGGUCUCAAACUCCUAACCUCAGGUGUUCCACCCGUCCUGGCCUUCCAAAGUGCUGGGAUUACAGGUAUGAGCCACCUCACGAGGCCCAGUAAACAUUUAUUUAAUCAGCCACAAAUAAAUGAAGUUGCAAAACUGGAGUGACAAGGACAGCCAGGAAAAUAUUUAACUUCGGUAAUCUUUACAAUGCUUCAAGUAGGUCCUGUGGAAGAACACUUAUUUGCUAUGAUGUAGAGGCUGAUGCAGGAAGAAAAAAGUGGUAAUAUUUAUAAGCUUUUCAAGACCAUUCGUUUAAAUAAGAAUAGCAGAAGCAGCUCCCCUUUCCCAAGCACAUACUCUCCAUCAGGCACUGUGUGCCUUCCAAACACCAUACUAUUAUCUUCCCCAUUUUGACAAUGAGGAAAUUGAGGAUUAGAGAACUUAAGACGAUUGUUGAAGGUCAUACACUAGGUAUCUUAGUAGCUGAUUCAGGAAUUUUUUGACAAUGAGGAAAUUGAAGAUUAGAGAACUUAAGACAAUUGUUUAAGGUCAUACACUAGGUAUUUUAGUAGCUGAUUCAGAAAUCCAAUAUAGUCUGUCUAACCACAGAGUCUAUGCACUUUACCAGUGGGCUACACUACUUUUUGUUGGUAUUUCUGUAUUUUAUGCCAGUUAAUUACUGGAAAUAGGGAAUAUAAAUUAUAUUCAGUUACAGGAAAAUGGUUAUUUAAGUUCAAAUAAUUUAACUCUGAUAGCCAAGAGUCAAAUUAUGUAACUAAUUGCAAUGACUCCUGUAAUUAAGGAAACGAUCAAAUUGAUUUUUCUAUUUUCUGUAAGGCAUUUUGAGUGGGAUACAAAACAAUUUUAGGCUUUAGUUGGGAAUGUAAGACAUGAAAAAUUAAACAGUCUUUCAAAAUAAUAGAAGAGAUGAUACAAAGUAGUACUAUAUGAUUCCUUCUCAAAUUAUUUAGACAAUUGUUAUGAUAAAGGUUAAGUUCCAGUGUAGUAAAAAACUAACUAGUGUGUCCAGGAAAAACUUUACAGAAAAAGUAAGAUUUAAACCAGGUCUGGAAAAAGGAAGGAGAGGAGGGCAUUUUAGAGAAGAGUAAAAAAAAAUCAUGAAUGUGCAAAAGGCCAACAAAAGAUCUUUUCAUGAUGAAAUGAGUCAUGCUUGUCCAAAACAGAAUUCAGAAAGGUGAGUAGUUGGAGAUAAGACUAAAAAGGUAGAUUAAGCCCUGUAUGAUUUUAAGACUCAUGAUUGCAGGUCACAGAACCUCAGCCUAAAUUGGCAUAAGUGAGGGGGAAAAUACAUGAAGGGGAAGGAGUAGCUCAGGUGAAUUGAAGAAGCAAGCACCGGGAAAGUGCUCCUGGAGUCCUUGAACAGCACUGGGAGGUCUCCACCUCCCAUCCCCUGUCUCUAAAGUGGCUACAUUCUCACAGCCUAUCUUUCUGUAGGAGCUGAAGCUCCAGUUGCCAGCAGCUGUCUUCCCUUAAUUCCAGUUGGAAAAAAUUCUAAGGAGGGCCAUGUGCCUGUUUGUAUCCAUCGGAUAUGGCCAGGAAGACAAGGGGGAUCUAUCCAGGCAGACUCAGCCAGGGGCCCUGAGGGAAAUCACUGGGAGCCAGGCCUGUAAUGGCCUUGAACGCCAGGUUAAGAGGGUUGAACGUGAUCUUUAGCUAAUUGAAAAGCAAGGUUAAGAUAGUGGGAAUAACAUGACCCAUUUUUCUACAAGCUUACUCUGUUAGUGAUAUAUAGGAUAUCCUUUCUUUAUUGAAUAUUACUGAAAUCGCCUUAAGCAUUAUAAGUAUGUUUUCAUUUCUCACAGUGCUCUUUUCACUAAUUAAUGGUUGACAAUAUUCAAAUAUUGGAUAUUUUUUGGAAAAGAAACCACUAAUUAAACAUCGUGGGCCAAAUUGGAAGUAUUGGUACAUACUGGAAGUGUAUUUAGUCUGAGUAAAAGUGAUGCUACUGCUUUUCUCAAUUCAUUGAGAGGAACAAAUUAUUUACAUAGAAAAGGAGAUAUACUUUAGCAAAUGUUUUAGAAGCUUGUCUUUUGAAAAAAGUUAUAGUGAUACAUGCACAUAAUUAAAAAAAAAAUAAGUUAGUUCUGAAGAGCUUAUAAUGGAAAUCAACCUUCCCUACUUUCCAGCAUCUUCUUCAGAGGCAACACUUUCAACUUCAGGGCUUUCUGGUAGUUACAACUCCAUAAACCUAAGUUCCUUCUUUUGUCAAAUGAGUCCCCAGUCAAAGGAUAAGGAUUUGAGAAACAUGCAUUUUACUUUCAGUUGAUUAGAAAUUGCCUGAUAUAAAUAUAAUUUAAAGUGUUAAUAGUCCUUUAUUU